AGAUGAAGAGGAGGCGGUGGCAGUGGUGGAAGAAGAGGCGGCGGCGGCGGGGGUAGGGAGCCUGGAAACGCGAGCGGGGAUGGUAGGUGGUUUGGACCCGCCGGGCCGCCGUCGUUUCCAGAAAGGGUUUGACUGGAGGAACCUCUGGAGCAGCUGUUGGCUGGCUCCUCUGGCUGAUGGCAUGUUGAGGUACAUGGGCCAGCGGCAGCGAGGGCAUCCAAUCCAGAGGGGUCCACUCUAGAGGCCAGGCCACCAGCACCAUGGGCCAGUGUGUCACCAAGUGUAAGAAUCCCUCAUCGACCCUGGGCAGCAAAAAUGGAGACCGUGAGCCCAGCAACAAGUCACAUAGCAGGAGGGGUGCAGGCCACCGUGAGGAGCAGGUACCACCCUGUGGCAAGCCAGGUGGAGAUAUCCUCGUCAACGGGACCAAGAAGGCCGAGGCUGCCACUGAGGCCUGCCAGCUGCCAACGUCCUCGGGAGAUGCUGGGAGGGAGUCCAAGUCCAAUGCCGAGGAGUCUUCCUUGCAAAGAUUGGAAGAACUGUUCAGGCGCUACAAGGAUGAGCGGGAAGAUGCAAUUUUGGAGGAAGGCAUGGAGCGCUUUUGCAAUGACCUGUGUGUUGACCCCACAGAAUUUCGAGUGCUGCUCUUGGCUUGGAAGUUCCAGGCUGCAACCAUGUGCAAAUUCACCAGGAAGGAGUUUUUUGAUGGCUGCAAAGCAAUAAGUGCAGACAGCAUUGACGGAAUCUGUGCACGGUUCCCUAGCCUCUUAACAGAAGCCAAACAAGAGGAUAAAUUCAAGGAUCUCUACCGGUUUACAUUUCAGUUUGGCCUGGACUCUGAAGAAGGGCAGCGGUCACUGCAUCGGGAAAUAGCCAUUGCCCUGUGGAAACUAGUCUUUACCCAGAACAAUCCUCCGGUAUUGGACCAAUGGCUAAACUUCCUAACAGAGAACCCCUCGGGGAUCAAGGGCAUCUCCCGGGACACUUGGAACAUGUUCCUUAACUUCACUCAGGUGAUUGGCCCUGACCUCAGCAACUACAGUGAAGAUGAGGCCUGGCCAAGUCUCUUUGACACCUUUGUGGAGUGGGAAAUGGAGCGAAGGAAAAGAGAAGGGGAAGGGAGAGGUGCACUCAGCUCAGGGCCUGAGGGCUUGUGUCCCGAGGAGCAGACUUAGUGGCUCUGUCCCAGGAGCAGCAGCAAGGAUCUGCCAGCUGCCCUGCAGCCAACUGAGGAAUUGGACCAUUUUGGAAAUUACUGAAGAUCCGGAUAUUUUCUACUUUACACCUUUCUCUGCCUUGUAUCUGAAAGGGCUCUAAAAUGCUGUAUCAUGUUUUAGGCACUUUCUUCAUUUUUUUGGUUAUUUUGGUUAUUUCCUUUUUGGGGGGAUCUCCCAGAAUAUUUGAACCUGGUUACAUGUUGUGUAUCUUUUUUUGAAGCCUUCAGAUAGAAUAAGCCUGCCAUUUCUUGCACAAAUUUAGGUUUUUUUUUUGUUUUUUUUUGUUUUUUUUUUUUUUUUUUUGGUAGGGGAGGGCAUAGAGCAGGGCGGGGGGAUGGGACUGUUAGGUUGAAUUAACAUUACAAAAUGAUACAGUGCCAGAUCUCAGUUUCGCAUAUUGUUUUUCAGGGCAGGUCUGUACUGUGUGUAGUGCUGUUUACAUAGAUGAAUUUAGGUUGUAAUAAUUAUUUUUAAAGAUUUACACAGAUUUGAAUAGCAGUGUUAACUGUUAACCACAUUGCAUUAAUUCCCAGGCGAUUUAGAGCUCUUGGAGAGCCAAGGCCAGCCAAGAGCAUUUGUAGUCUGGUGACAACCCCCUUUUAAGCUAAUUUAUCCAGAACCCUGAUUUCCCUCACUUCUUGCUCAUUCCUUCUUUGACCUAUUGCAUUUCAUGUUGAGUUUUUCCAUCAACAUGCUGCACCUGUCAGUCAAGUGAGCAUUUUUUAAGAACACAUUGUACUGAGAACCACUUAAGCAUUGAAUGCGGAGAAAGCAGUGCUACCUCAGUUUUGCUGGAAGUAGACUUCUUUGAUAGUUUUCUUUCUUUGAUGAAGUUUCUGUAUUUUCAUGUUGUAAGUGGAAAUACUUUUUUUUGUUUGUUUGUUUCAUUUGCCUUGGAGCCAAAGUUUCUGUUCCUGGUGGUCGGGAAACUGCCUGCCGGCCAACUGACUUGAAGGAAAACUGUGGUAUGGAGCUCUGCUUGAAUUUUUUUUUUUUUAAUAUUUUUAUUUUUUUCUUUGAAUAUCAUCAGCUUACUUGUCUGGCAAGGGCAGAAGCCUGGGGUUGGCCUGAACUCUGCCAAACAAAUAUCAAAGUGUAUUUAAUAGUUAAAUUUGUGCCCUUUCCCUUCUUGCUGCACCCAUGUUGUCACUUAACCCCCAGGAGUUAUUUAUUAUCUUUUUGUUAAAGUCAGGCUCAUUUGGGGUAAUGUGAUGACUGUUUAGGUUUACAUGACCCUCCUCUCCUUUCCCUACCCCCAAAUAUGUAUAUAUACAUAUAUAAAAUAUGUAUAUAUUUUACCUAUAUAAAAUAUAUAUAUAUACACAUAUAUGUAUCUAUAUUCCUUUGUUUCUUUGCCUGCUUAUACUGGCCAUAAAAGAGGGAGCUGCCUUCAAUGUAUAAAGUAUAAGAAGAGUGCCAGGGAAUGCCAUAAUGGAGGCUUUUGGAUCUGAAUUUGGACCAUUUCACUAAAGAGAACAUGAGUUUGCUCAGCCCUUUCCUCACAAGAGGGAGGGCCCCGGUUCCCCAGACUUCUCCACGCGCUGGCUCCAUAAAGGCCAGCUUUGGCCAGGCUGCCACAGGGGCCUGAGGAGCUCACUCUGGGCCUACCUGGUUUCAGUUAGAGGGUCCUCCUGUUAUUUUUCCAUUUAAAAAGUAUGUCCUCAGAAAACUGUACUGGAAGGAUGGGUGGCAGGAACUUGUAUAGUUCAGCUUCCAACACUUUGGAACAGAUUAAAAAGGGAAUCUUUUAAAUAAAAACGUAUAAAAAUAUUUAUACUCUUGAGGUAAUGAGACUUUGUCUGUUAAACAUUUGGAGGUUUCUCCCUUAACCUAAUACCCCGCUGCGUCCCAGGUAUGUUUCUCAGCCUGGGCAGGAAUUGCAUGUUUUGAGUUCCAUUGUGAGCAGCCUUACAGCUCUGGGCUCCCAUCUUAAGGAUUAUUAAAGAGUUUUGGCAGUUGGUAUUUUUCUAAAACUGAUAUUGACCAUAGGGAACAUACUUGGAAUUUGUUUUUUUUUUUAAAUCCUAAACCUGACAGUUCCUCCUUCAGAGGGGCAAAUGGGAAACUUUAAGAUCACCCACGGUAUAGUACUGCUAGAAAGCUGAAGGGGGUCUUGGGCCAGAUGCCUGGCUUCUGUUCUAGCUAAAUAAGACUCUUGAAUAAGUCUCCAGGGGUCCCAGCAGGUUCUGUGGGAUCAGUUGUAGCUGGGUACCCAGACUGAGGUUUUAAAAAGACUGCUUUUUCAUUAAGCCAGUUUGCAACUCAUUUUCCCCGGUUCUGGAUUGGGUAGUGGUUGACUGAGGGAAAAGCCAGGCUGCUCUUGGCCAGAUAAGGCCCUUUCCAUCCCAGAUCAGAGUGUAUCAGAGAAAGCUGCACAAAAGAGGCAGGCAGCCCAGGACCCUGAGUACUCUGGAGAAACUAGGUUCCUUCCCCACCCUUUAAGAAGACAUUCCGUGCAUUAGAUGUACUAGAGUGGAUGUAUUUUGUUGUUUUUUAAAUUAACUAUUUAGCCUCCUCAUCCCCCACCAAAAAAGCCAUUUAGUUAUUUUUUGGUUAUAUUGAUCCAUUUGCAAAUGAGAAGCCAGAAAAGGGAGCAGUCAGGGAGGGACUUACAAGUUCCUUUCAAGUUUGAGUACUUGAUGCUCAGCAAAGAUUUCAAGCUUCUGCAGUAGCUCUGGGCCAAUGCUUGACUCUUUCAUGACCACAAGAAAUGCAGUUUUUCUGCAAAGGGAUCCAAGGUGAGGUGUGUGUAGGGUUUGAAGUUAUACUUCUGGGAAGUGAAAAGUCUUGUUCCUUUCAACCUAGAAAUAGGUUUGCCACUUAAUGAGUGAGCAGUAAGUCUGUGUAAGAGGCUGAAUGCAUGCCCCUCAGAUAAGCCAGUACACUCCUUGCUUAGCAACAGAACAUCAGGGUGAUGUGGAGAGGGGCAGGAUGUGGACGCCACUUUGGAAAUCGGCAACAUCUGAGGGCAACAACAAACAAGUGUGUUGGGAAAUAAGAAAUAACUCAGUUUUGACAACUGGCUUUGUCAGCUUUUGUGAUGUUUCUUUAGCAGUUUAUUGGAAAGAUGGUAUGAGAUGACGUGCUGCUUCAUUGAAUUGCUCUUUCCCCCAUCUUUGCCAAAUCUCAAUGUAUCGUUCUUAACCCCACCUCCUGUAAGGGGCUUUGCUAUGCUUCAGCUGGUUGUCUCAGCAGCUGAAGUGCUGCCCACCUGUGUGAGUUGGGUCCAGGAAACCAUGUCUGCCCUUCUGAUAAGGGAAGAUGAAUCUAGAGCUGGGUGAAGAUCUAAAUUUUAACCAAACCCCUGGGCCCAGGAAAAUAACAAUUGAAAAUGUACAAGGCAGUGUUUUCAAUAUUAAACUUCCCCAAGGAAAGCACAAACUAGUCUUUUUGGAAAGGGAGAAAGGAUUAAGCCACACAGUAUUAGUCUUUGAAGCAGUACUGGUCUCUAGGGGCUGGUGCCAAAAUGGAGUCCCAUAGUAGUUACACUCGAUGGCCUCAUGUACUAUAUACUGUGCCAAAUUGUAUUAAACAGUGGUGGGGAGUUACUGGGAUAAGAACUUGUCUAAAAGUUUACAAACCAAAACAGAUCUGUUAGGUUGGUGCAAAAGUAAGUUUUUGCCAUACUUAAUGUAUUGCCAUUAAGUAUGGCAAAAACCACAAUUACUUUUACACCAACCUAUGUAUUUAAGAAUGUUUGGUUUGCCAGAUUCCAAAUGAGGUCUUCAGUGCAGCAAAGCCCAAAAGGUGUAGACUCAGUUAUGCAAUUAUAAGGUUAAGGCGUAGAAGAAAGCUGCUGCUAGGUUUUUGUUGCAUUUUACUUGACUGCUCUGCUGUUUUUCUUGUCUCUCAUGUUUGGUUAGCUAUGACUUGAGCAUCUUGGUAACUGACAAAGGUCUUCCUUGGGGGACUUGAACAUCUUGGUAAAUGACAGGUCUUCUUGGAGGACUCCAGCAGUAUCUUGUUUAAACGACUGAAAGGACUAUUAAGGUUGUUGAAUUGUGUUAAUUGGGACUCAUUGAGGAAAUGCGACAUUGAUCCUCCUCUUAUUCCACAGUGUGUUUUCUGAUCAUAUAAAGAAGGUUCCGAACCAUCCAUCCCCCUCAGAGUUUAUUCCCCUGGUAAGCUGUAAUUGCAUAUCCAGUUUAAACUGGACUGGGACUGCAUGUUGGUGAGGAUCGGCAGGGGUUUUCCCCCUUUUCGAAAGAUGAAAUAGAUUCUUGAGCACUGGUUGCAGAAGCCAAAAUAGUUCAAAUAGCUUUGCAUAACCAUUGGGUUCUGCUUCUGAUUCAGGUGCUGGGCAUCAUGUCCUCCCUAUUCUUCUCUUCUUGGAAACCCAGCCUAUCUCAUAAAUACCUACUUCCGCCACCCAUCCAACCUCCCUGCUCCUUUCAACACAAAUCUUGGAUAUUGCCAAAGGAAGCCAUUCAGCAGCUGCUGGGGUUUUUCAUCCCCCUGACAUGCAUACAUUUGCUCUGGGAGAAGUGUCUUCCCUCUGACCCUGGUCCCCAGCUCCGUCUGUGCUUAAUUGCUCUUACCUGUUGCACUAAUGAAUAUGACUAGGUUUUAAAGGGGGAAUGUGAAGCAAUAGGCACAUGGGGCUUGGAUGAAUUGGUCCCACAGAUAUACCCUGCCUUAAGCCGCUGAGGUGAUGAGUCCACUGCUCAUGUGACCCUCCACCUUUGUGGAUCCCUCUUGGUUUGUGACCAGUGUGUCUGUUUGUUGAGGUUGUACAAACUUGACAAAAGUUAAUACUUUUGUUUGUAUUUUCUGCACUGUUGCACUCUCCAAAUGGCCCCUUGAGUAUUUUUAUUGACUUGUUACACACAUUUUUGUCUUUGAUGUCUACAUUUUUUCCUUUAAUGUUUUUUAUUUGGAAGGUUACCUGCUGUUGGAUUUAAUAAAUUUGUUUACUUGAA